UUGAAGCAACUGUUUUAUUUUAUAUUUGCCUCAUUUGUAAGUGAUGCCUCAACAUAAAUACAUUUUGCAUUUGAAGUCAUUGAAAACUACUAUAUUUGCUAAACAGUUAUAUUCCAAUCCUAUGUUUCCUCAACCUAAGCUCUUAGAGUCAAAAAGUUGUAAAGCAAUUUUAUACUGUACGAUGCCUCUAUGAAAAGAGAUUUUUCUUUACUUUACCACAUGAAAUAUGUGGUAAUUGACAAAACAUGUUGUAGUUAAGGACAAAUGUGGAAAGUACAGCCCCAGAUUAUAGCAAUACACCUUUAUUAGAAAGAAGUCAGGCUAUCUGAUCUCUUCCUGCAAUGCAAAACUGUCUGAAGGCAUUGAGUAACUCAGUACCAGAGAAAAUGGAUUGUACCUGCCCAGAUGGAGGCAGAAAUGCUCAUGGUGGUGUUGUAAAACAAGCUCCUAAGCAGCAAAGAGACACUGAGCUGUCUGUAGGGAAGUGAAAAAGAACUGCAAAUUAAGCAUGCCAUGGUUAUUCACUCUUUUAUAUUAGUGUCUCCAACUCCGAUAAAUGCUGUUUAGGGUUUUCACGUACUCAAAACUGUCAUUUAAUCUGAAAUGAUGUUGUUACAUAUUUGAGAGUCAUUUUGAAAACUUACUGAAAAGGAUCUGACAUCAUACCAUGGAGUAUAUGGCUAGGGACAUUGUGGCAGUUUAUUUGCCACGGCAAGUUUAAUCUAAAUCAGCAAAUAUCUAAUUUCUCAUGAAAAGUGAAAUUCCAGGAGGUUUUUUCCUCCACAGUGUUAUUAAAUAAUCUGAGUUCUGCCAGAAGAAGGAAUGGCUCAUGUGGAAAAUAUUUAAUUGCCUGCAUUCAUAUGACAGGAGUGUUCUGAAUUUAAAUAACAUAUAAUGAAAAGCAGUAGAGUAAUAUUGCCAAGAAAUACCUUCUCACAGGUGAUUGACUAAUCCCUAGAGGAUUCUGUGUGCCGUACAUUAGCCUGGUAAAAGGGAACUGGGCUAAUGGUCAGUCUUAAAUCCGGACUGUGAAGCCUAAUCCUGAAUUUGCCAUUGGUUGACCACAGAAAUUUAAAUUCCUCCCUCCAUUUUAAUUUUCUCUCCCUUCCUCCUUGUAUCCUUCCCUUCUUCCCUAUCUCGAUAAUUUCUAAAGAAUCUACUAUGUAAUAGCAUCAUGUUAGAUACUGAGAUACAAAGAUAAAAGAUACUUCUGCCUUGAAAGGAGCUUAGGGGAAGAACUGGUCGGGUCAAAUCAUAUAAUUCAGGUCCCUUGAAGUUCUGAUAUCCAAUCCUUUGCUCCUGUUUAAAUUCUUAUCACAUAGUCAAUGUCAUUUUUUGAUUGCUUGGAAAUAAUGAAUCUUAAAUGCGAGGUCAUAGCUGGCUUGCAAGAGUCAUUAAUAUAUUCAAUAAAUAUUUUGAGCCCUAUGGGAUGCCAAGCAUUUUGCUAGAAGAAACAUUAUAAGAAACAGGUACCAUGUGAAAUGGGAGCACAGAGGAGGACCACACAGUCUUCUCUUAGGAAUUCAAGCCAGGGUUUCAAGAGAGUGGAGGUCUAAGCCAAACCCUGAAGGAUAAGAAAGAGUGUGGCAGGCAGAGGAAGCAGUACCCCUUGUGCAUGAGAAGUACCCCUUGUGCACUCAAGGCAAAGAACAGUGUGUGCUUACAGGAAUGCAAAUUGUGUUUGUGGAAUUGCCAGUCACUAGGCAUCCCUGAAGAACAAAGUGUGAAAAGGGGUAGAGCAGGGAUAGAUGACCUCGAAGUUGAUGCAAAGAAGUGAUGAAUGGCCAUUCAAAGGAUUUGGGGCUUUAUCCUGAGGACACUGGAGCAGGUCUGGCAUGAUCAGAUUUGAAUUUAGAAUAACAAAUUAAAAACAAACAAUCUUCUCAGAAAGGUGUUAAGGAAAUGAGGUGAAGAUCAGACAUCUAUCCAUUAAUUUUUUCCAAGCAAGAUGACUUUCUGUUUUAGGUAUGAAUCUUAGUCUCAAUCUCAGGGGUGUUAAAAUUUGUUCUUUAUAGUUUAUUUAAUUUGUAUUUUGUAUUUAUAUUUCCACAAGCUAUAAAAAUAUUAACGUAGACCAUUGGCGCAGUUUGCACUCUCACUCAGCUUUGCAGUGUUGUGACAUAAUACUUAGGAUUUAUGUGUGCCAUGAUGUCAUGGGGGAAAGAAAUGUGGAAAGUUGUCCAUGCCGAUAUUGAAAGAUUUAUGGUUUCCUUUGUAUAGCUCCUCAGGAUCAGUAAUAAAACUUACAGACUGGGACUAUUUGCUGAGGCCCUCCAGAUAUGUCCAGGCCUCAGUUCCUUGUCCAUUUUCUGGGUAACUGUCAUUUCCUGAGAACUCUAGCUGCCUUCUCUGAGGAUAUGGAACCCUCCUCCCAACCCUCUCUCCUCAGCCCAGUUGAAACUUCAGCCUGAGGCUAACAUUUUAUUCCUUAUUGUUUCUUCCAGUGUGCUUUUUCUAAUACUCUUUUAUCCCUCCUAUGCAUUAGCAAACACUUUUAAUUAUCCUAAGCAUUUAAGCUUUUGAACAACAAAAGCCAAAAAGAACUGAACUCUGCUUGGGCUGAGUCUCUAAGUAAACUCACUCUCUACUGUGUCAUGUAUCUCCCCUUAGGGAAUAAGGUGUGGAGCAGGCAACCCACGUGAAGUGGGCUAAAAGUCAUGUGAGAGAGAAACAGAGGUAGAAAAACGCAAACUAAAACAAGUAAAUAUCUCAAAAUAUCAUCUAGCUUCACCUGCUUUGUAUGCUAUUUCCCCUCUGCUUUUGUUGAAUUUGAAAUUGCUUUUGUUGAAUUCCCUAGUUUACAGUCUCCACUCUCAGUUAUUUCAUGAACAUUUUCUUUUGUGCAGCCCACUGCACUGACCUAUUCACAUGCUGUUUCCGUUUUGCAGUCUUCUCUUGGUACCACCACAAGCUGCCUCCUGAAACCCCUGGGCAGGAGUGCAGAAGCUCACUUGAGCUCACAUACGGGGCCGAUUGCGCUGCCUAGAACUCACUACCCUGAAAGGCUAUUCUUAGAUUCCUCAUCUAGUGAGGGAAUUGCACUAUUUCAUGUCAGAAGUGUACCAGUUAAAAACAAACAAACAAAAAAAAGAAUUAGGAAUCUAGGACCCUUUUAAAUUAUUCUCCUGCUACCAUUAGAAAUCCUUUUAUCCUAUCCACUGUGUUUUUCAUGUCCUGGCCAAAGCAAAACUAUAGAGAAUGAAAAUCUCCACUUUUACAGUUUCAUUUAGCAGGGAAAUGUUCUCAGUGCCUGAGUGGAACCUCAGUGCCUGUGUGGGAACCUCUAAAACUGUGUAGCUAAUUUCCAAAAAAUUUCCAAUAUAUUUAUUUAAAAAAAAACACAUAUAAGUGGACCUACACAGUUCAAACUCAUGUUGUUCAAGGGUCAACUAUCGUAACGACUGAGUAAGAGUUAGGAUAGGUAUAUCCUUCUUUUAGACCAAAAAUGAAAUAAUAUUGAUACUAAUUUAAAGUUCACAUACUUAGAUAGCUAUAAAAGAAUUUAUUCCAUGAGAAUAUUACCUUUGCAUGUGUAUAUAAAAGUCUCUGUAGCUAUGUGCAAACUUGGAAACAUAAUAAUUAGUUAUAUAAAAGGGUUUUGAUAUAAAAAGGCUUCAGUAAAGUUUUCUAAGGCAACAGAAUACUUUUUUAAGUUUAACAGAAAUUAAUUCAAAUACUAAUUCUGUGGCUUGUGAAACAAGAAAUCUUGGAUAAAUGACUAAAUCUUUGUGAAUGUCAACUUAUUCAAAAAUAGAGAAUACCUACUCUGUUUUGCAAAGACUAAAUAAGACAAUGACUACUUUCUGGCACAUUGUAGUGUUUAACAAACAGUUGUUAAUUUAUUUAUUGAAAUGACCGCAGGGCAUGUUGGUUAAGAGCACAGACAAUUUACCUGGGCUGCUUGUCUCUGAAUCACAACUCUGUCACUUAUGAGCUAUGUGGCCUUAGGCAGAUGACUUAACUUCAAUGAAUGUCAGUUUCUUCAUCUGUAAAAUGUGGAUGAUAAAGAGCACUGGCCUCAUAGAGUUGUGAAAAAGAAAUGAAUUAACAUAUAUAAAUGCCUACAGCAGUUUUUAGCACUAAGCAAGCAUUAAGCAGGUGUUAGCUCUUAUUAAUAUUCAAUAGAUGAGAUAAGGGUAAAAGGAAGUAAUAUUUAUCCAGUGUAUUACACACAAACUAUUGUCUUCAACUUAUUUACAUUAUCUCAUAUAAUCCUUACAGCAGUCCUGAGGGGUAAGAAUUUAUUUCCCUAUUUUUCAGUUCAGGAAAUAGAUUUAGAGAACCAAAAUCUCUCCAGUAUACUAAAUCAUCCAUCUCAAUUAUUUAAAUCCUUCUCUUUUCCCUUUUCUCUUGUUAGAUUAGCUCUUCAUCUAAGGAGUAGAUAUUACAUGGGUUUAUUGGUUUACCUUACCCUGUUUUCUCAGUCUGUUCCAUGUAAAGUUCUAGAGCUCAUUGGGAGAGUCUUUGGUCUGAUGCUCUUGUCUAAUCUGUAUUCACAAUGCCCCUAACACUUAAAAGUCUAUAGAGAAAGCAUAGAAUGAAAGGGUAAUUCAUCAAUGGUAAUUCAGAUCUAUCUUAAGUGCCCCCACCUGCUCAUAGUGCUACAUUCAAUCAUUUUUCAAAUGUGUCCCUUUAUGGUUUGGGGCACUAUUUACCAGGCACAGUACUUUUUAUACCUGAUGAUAUAAGCCAAAAAGAUAUGUUCUCUUUUUCAGGAGAUGUACAAUCCAGUUUGAAAGACAAAUGCAAAAGAAACUAAACAACAAUAAAAUAUAAAUCAAUAAUUUGGGAUAUAUGCUGUAAGAAGAAAAAACAGCAGGUGCUAGAGAAAGAAUAUCUAUGUGGACAGAGGACAGAAUAAUUUUGACAGACAGUAAGUAAAGAGUUCUCAGUGGAGGUGACAUUUCAGUGGAAGCCUGAGGGAUGAGGAGAAGACAGCCAUGAAAAGGUGGGCAGGGAGUGUAAGUGAAAAAGUGUAUCUGAGUUGCCUAGACAAUUAGAAUAACUGAGAAUACAGUUCACUUCCAUUCUACUUCAACUGAAUUUAAAGCAGGUGAACUAAAUUACUCUUAGAAGUUUGUUAAAUAGAGCAUGAAGUAGAACACCACAUAUAUAGUUAAGCACAGUAACUUACGUACACAUUAAAAAUAGACGUUAACCAUAUUAAAAAAAGCAAGCCCAUAUCCAGGUGUCCCAGCAUUCAAACCAGCAUGCCUUUUAGACAAAUGACAAAUCUGUAUAUCCUUGUGGCAGGGGUGAGGAAUUCUAAACCUUUCUGUUUUGCAAACCAGGCUUCCUCAUUUCUGCUUUUAGAUUAUAUCUUUGUCAUGUCAGCAUAUGUAGGGGUUAAUUGAGGUGAUGGAGUAGCCUCUUAAUGUAGGCAUUGUUCUAAAGCCCAUAUUUAAGGCAAUGGCUGUUAAAAAGCAAUGUGAUAAAACUUCACUGUAGUUAUUCUGAUCUAUGAAGCGAAUGGUUUCUUUUUUCUUUUCUUUUCUUUUUUUGAGACAGAGUCUUGCUCUAUCCCCCAGGCUGGAGUGCAGUGGCACGAUCUCGGCUCACUGCAACCUCUGCCUCUCAGGUUCAAGCAAUUCUCUUGCCUCAGCCUCCCAAGUAGCUGGGACUACAGGCAUGCGCCACUGUCCCCGGCUAAUUUUUGUAUUUUUUAGUAGAGAUGGGGUUUCACCAUGUUGGCCAGGCUGGUCUCAAACUCCUGACCUCAUGAUCCGCCAACCUCGACCUCCCAAAGUGCUAGGAUUAUAGGUGUGAGCCACCACACCUGGCUUAACCAAAUGGUUUCUUUAGAGAAUACCCAGAUCAAAGGUUGGACACUGCAGAGAAUUUCCUCAUUUCACUGCCUUUUUAGGGUCCCCAUUCCCACUCAGGGGUGAGACUACUUCAAACAGCCAUUAGCUCUGGACCCAAGGUCUCUAUGUGGCAUAAACUCACUGCUUGUAAGUGAAAGAGUUUUGUGUUUUCAGUUAUCCUUAAAGAGAUAAGUCACAAGAGCUUCUGUGAAUGAAAGCAAUUUAUUUGUCUUCUAUAGCUGACUUGAGAACAGCUGUCCUUACAAAGUUCAAAAGUUACCAAAACCACCAUCAGUUUUGAUAAUUCACUAGAAGAACCCACAAAAAUCAUGGAAAGCUGUAAUACAGUAUAUAGUUAAUAGUUUAUCACAGCAAAAAGAUACAGAUUAAAAUUAUCCAAGGGAAGAGAUACAAAGAGAGCAGAGUCCAGGAGAGUUCCAAAUGCAAAGCUUCCAGUUAUCCUUCCCCAGGGAAGUCAUGAAGAAUGCUUGUUUUUCUGCAAUGAUGUAUCACAGUUUGCAUGGGGUAUUACCCACCAAGGAAACCACCACGCCCCAGUGUUGAGUUUUUACUGGCACUUGGUCACAUAGACAUAUUAGACUGACUGUGUGGCUGACCUUUAGUCUCUAGACCCUCUGGGCAGGGAGCUGAUACCUGGCCCAAAACUCCUAUCGUUAGUCAUGUAGUUACAUCACUGGCUCUGGUUCAAGAUCCCCAGGUAAACAAAGAUAUUCUUAGCAGAAAGGACAUUCCAAAGACUUAGAGAUCACCUCUCAGGAGCCAAGAACAAAGGCAAGACUUUUCUCUGGGGAAGGGUUAUUCUAUUUUAAAAAGCGUUUAAAUUUUAUUUUUUAACCAAUAACAAUUGUAUAUACUUAUGGGGUACAAUGUGAUGUUUGGAUAUAUGUUUACAAUGUGGGAUGAUAAAAUCAGGCUAAUUAACAAAUUCAUUGAUUCACAUGCUUACCUUUUUUGUGGCAAAAAUAUUUAAAGUCUACUCUUAGAAAUGUUGAAAUAUACAAGCCAAACAUAGACUGAAAGUGAAGGGAGGAAGAAAGACAUACCAGGCAAAUGGAAACCAAAGGAGAGAAGGGGUGGCUAUCUUUAUAUCAGACAAAAUAGGCUUUCAGUCAAGAACUAUAAAAAGAGACAAGGUCAUUAUGUAAUGAUAAAGAGGUCACUUCAUCAAGAGGAUAUAACAGUUUUAAAUAUAUAGGCACCUGACAUCGGACACAUAAAUGAUUAAUUAUUACACAGUGUUGCUCUAAUAGAAAACAUUUAUGUACAGCAAAGCUAUAAAAAAGCUUUUUAAAUAUAAGCUUGAUCAAAGGAAGAGUAGUAUAACAUGUGUUGAUUGUCAUUUCCCUUCCAAACAUCUAUAGUUGGGACAACUGUAUGGAACUGAUGUUAUUACCUGCUGGACUGCACUAUAAACCAGGUUUUGUUUGUUUGUUUGUCUGUUUAUUUGAUUUUUCUGAUAGGAAGAAUAAGGCCAGGCAUGGUGGCUCAUGCUUGUAAUCCCAGCAAUUUGGGAGACUGAGGCUGGCGGAUUGCCUGAGUCCAGGAGUUUGAGACCAGCCUGGGCAACAUGACGAAAUCCUGUCUCUACAAAAAAUACAAAAAUUAGCUGGGCAUGGUGGUGCGGGUCUGUGGUCCCAGCUAUUUGUGGGGCUGAGGUGGGAGAGUCACUUGAACCUGGGAGUGAGAUUGAACAGUGAGCUGAGAUUGCACCACUGUUCUCCAGCCUGGGUGACAGAGUGAGACUCUGUCUCAAAGAAAAGAAAAAGAAAGAAUACUUACCCAGAGCAAAUCACUUGCGCAAAGGCUGGAGGCAAAAAAAAAGUUUGGGAAACUGAAAGAAACCAGGGGAGUUAAAGUAUAGUACACAGGGCACGUGCCAAGAUGCUUAGAUUGUAUUCAAAGUGCAAUUCCACUUCUUUGUAGAGGCUUGAGUAGUGACAUGGUCUUAUCUACAUUUGAAAAUAAUAAAUCUAGCUGUUAUGUGCUUCUUAAAAAGCAAAGUUUUCUAGACCGAGCAUGAUCAUGUGAGUCUGUGACAGUGCCUACCUCUUUUCCCCCAAAUCAGAUCCCUUUUUAUUUCCUGUACAGAGCUGGCUCGUUGGAUAUUGCCAAGUGUAACAGUUAUUUACCCCCUCUUUACUUGCAAAUAUUAUUUGGUCACUCACUAGUUAAUAAUUGGCCUAUUUUAUAGAGUAGCUCUGAGGGCAUCUUUGGUUCCACCCAGAAGUUCUCUGGUUGCUUUUAUGACUAGACCAGGUUUUUCCCUCUGGUGCCUCCUUCAUUAGUAAUUGUUAGUUGAUAGUUCCUAAGUGGAACGCUUCUUUCUUAUGUCGUCUACAUUCAAUUAUCCCGAGUGGCCUAUUCCCAUCCUGUUGUAUGCCAAGUAAUUCAUUUCUUUUUUCCUUCCAGGAUUCACUCUUGGAACAUGCCAAACCAAGUCCCAAACAGAUGUCUCUUUUUCAGAUACUUGGCAAAAGAUUUUUGGUGGAUCAGUUUUUAGUGGUCCACAGGGGCUAAAAGAUUUUUUCCUCUUAUUUAUUCUAAAAGCUUCUAAACAGAAAUUUGUUCUGUAAGAGAAUCCACAUUACUAAACAAGACACAAAUACUGCUCCAAAAACAAAGCAACCAUCAAUAACUUGGAUUUAAAAGCCACUCGUGAGAUUCUGAAAAUUCAGUCUUUCUGUGAAAGAGCUGACUUGAGUACUCAUUAAGAGCCAAUGUCUCUGGGGAGCUCUGCUAUAACUUUGCAGAAUUAGUUAGGGAAAUGUAGUCACCAUCAUCUAACCAUCUAUAAGAUAAAGAAUAGUUUUCCUGGGCUGAAAAUCAGUUUUCCCGGGCUGAAAGCAGGGUGCCAGCAGGGCUGAGAUCCCACAAAAUACUUUGGGAGAAAAUCCAUUUCCUUUCAUUUCUCAGUUUCUAGUGCCGCAUUUCUUUCAUUCCUUGGCUGCUGACUCUCUCGCUUUUCAAAGCCAGCCAAGUAGCUUAACCUUGUACUUCAAUCCUUGCGUUGUAUUCAUCUUUAAUGGUUAAAUCUCCUUCCACCUCCCUUUUAUAAAGACAUUUAUAUUACAUUUAGGGUCCACCUGCAUAGUCCAAAAUAAUCUCUCCAUCUCAAGAUUCUCAAUAACAUUUGCAAAAUACUUUUUGACAUAUAACAUUCGCAGCUUCUGGUUAUUAAGACGGGCAUAUGUUUGAAAAUCAUUAUUCAGCCUACCAUAAGCUAUGCACAGCUCAAGAUCCUUUUCUAACCCGUGUCGCAAAGUAGUGACACUUAAUUAACAAAAAGUGUUUAAAGGGUUUUAUAGGCUUUAAAUACUUAAUAUCAAUAAAUGCUUGUUUGUUCAUUCAUUCACUUAUUUAUUCAUUCUUGAUCCCAUUUACUGUUUUAACCCCAGGAGUUACUGUGAAAAUAAAUAACUGAGAUAUGAUUUUAAUUUAGCCAUGAUUUACAAUAAGGUUAUUACGCAGUUUAAUUAUUUCCUGUGGUUAACUGCUCCUUUUACUUACAGUGGAUAUCCAUUGAGCAAGAACAUAUUUUUGCUUCCUUAAAUAACUCAUUGAAACUUAUCAUCUAAAAGUUUGAAUGUCCCCUUGUUUUAUUUAAAAAAAAAAAUCUGACUCUUUGCAGAGUAACUGUACCCUUCCGAAUUUAUCAAUGCAUGCGGAGACAAUGGUGCUUUCAUCUAUUAGAAUUCUUUCUGUCACAAGUGAUACAAAACACAACAUGCACUAGUUUGAACACGACAAAAUAGUGUGUUACCUACUCAGAUAAUUGCAAUGUUCAUUGUGGGACUGGUUUAUUGGUGAAAGUCAAAGCUAGAAGCAGAUGGAGUACUCACAUUGGGUAACUUGAGAAAUAGUAAUGAAAGAGGAUAUGCAGAAAUGUGGAGGAAGUGUAUAGGGAAACCAUAAGAUACAGUGCAAUAGUCUAAUGCCUGUACACAAAGAGCUGUUACAAAGUCCAGGGCCUGGGGGAGGGCAUGGGGCAGUGACAGGAACCUAGAGACUGAUCUACAUGGAGAAGACCACCUGCCAAGAGCUGAGAUUUUAGCUAAGGUGUGCAGCAAACCUGAUUCAACACCUCAGGGAAGAAUCCAGGAUAAUAAAAUAGUCUCACUUUAUUUUCUUCCUUCUCUGCAAUCUCCUGCCGAUGUUUACAAUUUGAAACUAACUUGAAGUCAGAGGUAAAGAAGCUCCUUGAUACCAUCCUUAUAAAUGCACUCUCCCAGUCCAGACACUGAACAAGAUGGAAUAACUGGUGAGUGGAUGUGGAAGGAUGAAUGGAAGUUACUGACGUGCUGGUUUAAGACACAGAUGAUUUUAGGAUCUGAGGGUUAGCUUAUCUCUCUCUCUUCCUCCUUGCUCCGCUCUCUUAGCUGUGCUCCCUUCCCUGUUUUCUGCAUAGUCUCAGAUGGACUUUACUGCUCGAGCUACCAAGAUAAUUGCAGCAGGUCCCCACAUCACAAUUCUAAAUGCUGAAAAAAGAAUACCUUUUUCUAAUCAAGUAGUUUUGGCAAAAUCUGCAAUAAUUUUAUCUGUGUGACGGGAUGACCUACCUGUCUCAGUCGGUCAUUGUGGUUAAGAGACUUCAAGACUCUGAUUGGUCCUACGAAACUCAUUAUUGCCUCUGGGGUGGGGGUGGAAUCAGGUAUGUGGGACUAUGUGAUAUGAGAGAAAAGGAUGGAGGGAUUCACAAAUGAAGAGCCUACAUUUACAGGUGAAAUAUGAAUAGAUUCUGGAUAGUCAGUGCCUUAUUAUUUUUCCAGUGAUUAGAAAUGUUUGUCUCUGAAACUGCUUAAUAAAAGAUUAACAUUUUCAUUUUGUUUAACAUCUUUUUUCUCACUAUGUCCAAUAUAAGCCACCAUUUUUAGAAAUACGAUAAAGCUGCCUCUCAAUUUUUUUCCAUUCCCGCAUGUGUCAUAAAGGUGAUUUGGCUAUCAUAUUGUAAUUCCAUUUUCUAUCAUUGCUUACAUGUUUUUCAGUGAGUAGUUAAUACUUCCUAAAAAUGCAUAUAUUUUUGUACAGUUUUAUAAUUUUCAUAGUGUCCAUUUGUAAUCUUCAUAACCAUCUUAUAAUGUAGGUAUUUUAUCUCCACUUUGCAGAUCUGGAAAUGUUAGCUAAAAAGAGAUUAAGUGACCUGCUAACAAAUUUUAAGUGUGUGGCCAGGGGUUUAAACUAAGGCUUUUCUGAUCCUAGACAAGUAUGUGUAUAGAAACAAUUUAAGAUUCGGUUAUGUAGAUUUGUGUGCGUGUGUGUGUGUGUGUAUCUGGAUAUAACAAAGGCCACCGGCUCUGACAUUUGUGAUUUCACAAGGACUUACUACAUUCUUUUUUGCAAAAUAUGCUCCUUCAUGACCCAUUACUACAUAAGAAAAUUCCAAAGCAUUAUUUAGUAGCAAUUUCUUUGAGAAUGUUUUGUAGAUAUGUACAUUUGAGUAAAAUAGAAAAGUAUUAACUAGGAAAGGGUAAUGAUAGUUUCUAGCCACAUUUGUAUUAACCAAUUUAUAAGACUGAUUAUUUCCUAAUAAAAAUGAAAUCCUGAGGGAAUGUGACAUAAGGCACAGACUUUUUGUGAACAAAGGAUACAAGGAAAAGUGAGAACAGAGAUAUUUCCCUGUUCAAAAGAGGAAAUCCAGUUAUAUUAAUAGCAAAGCUGAGCUUCUGAACUUAAAAAUUUUAUUAUAUAUAUAUAUUAUACUAGUCCUCUAUAAAGAUGCAACUGUAUUAUGAAAUCAAAUUAUUUAUUGGUACCAGACUUCAUCAGGUGCAUUAAGAAAAAAUGUUCAAAUCUUUAAGGAGACUUUUCUGUAACCACCUGUGUAGAGGUGACUUACAACGUCUAUGCCUUUGAGUAAUUUCACUUCUGAGAAUCUAUUUUAAAAGAAUCAUCUUAAAUAGAGAAAUAUGUAUAUUUACAGGGUGAUGAUUAGCAGUAAUUGAUUUUAUAAUAGGAAAUAAAUGUUCAAAAGAGGACUGGUUAAUAAACUACAGUGUAACAAUUUGUGAUGUCGUAGUAUUUUUACUGAUCUCAUAUAAAGUAUAGAAAUAUUCACUCAUUUAAAUUAAAUGAGGAAAGCAUAAUACAAAUUACAUUAUAGCGUGAUUAUACCAAUGUAAAAUAUGUGUUUAGCAGAAGUCUAAAAGGAUAUAAUGUUUAAAGUUAGCAGUGGUUGUGUGGGCCUGCCAUAGCUAUGGAUUUUUUCCCUUUUUGUUUUCAUUUUUAGAAAUGUCUAUAAUGUUUAUACCAGUUUUAUAAAGAAAAUAUAUCACUGUAAUACACUGGUAAAAGUAACCUUCUUUGUCCUUGUAUGCUCAUAUAAUCUUUUGCAGUGUACUACUGAAUAAAAGAAUGUCCAUGCCUGCACCCCUAGCUUUGAGUCCAUUGCCUAUGACACAUACACCUGUGAUUUCUGAUUGUGGUCAUUUUGCACAAAAGAUACAUGAGUCUGGCUGUUUUAAGAUUGACUACUGGUCCUUGUGUGCUGCUGAACCAGGACAUAACAUCAAGUGAUGUUACUUAUUCAUAAUAAUUCAUAGCAGAUUUCAUGCUAUGUUAUACAUGGCACUUUUUGGGAAAAGGAAUCAGUAGGAAGAGAUUGUAUAAUGAAGUUCCCUGGGACUGGCAUGUAGGUUUGCCAACUACUGAGGCAGAAAAUGUAGUAAAUGAUAAGAAAUGUGUCCCCAGUUGUCAUCAUCAUCAUCAUACGGAUUCAUGGCUGAACCUUCAAGCAUGACUGCAUGAUAGGUUAAAUGGAAGUAAACUCAUUAGACGUGUCAGCUUCACUUCAUUAAUAAUGAGAAGUAGUUCAGCCAGUGCACUUGUACAUCUGGCGAUGCUCUGUGGCUCAUAUAUUUUGAGUUGUAGGAAGACAAAUAUCUCCCAGACACCUGAGGGGAAUGUAAGGUAAGCAACAAAGGAAUGUCUGCAUUGAAGUAUUAGUUAAGUAAUUUUUACCUAUUUUCACGGAUUGAAGCUGAAGCCUCUAUAAUUGAACAUACUGGAUACAGUGCACCCAUCCUGUUACUUUAAAUAGAUGUUUGGGGCAUAUUUUCUCCUUAGCUUAGUCUCUUUGUUGAUUCCCUUGAAUCCAUACAAUGAGCUAAUAGGGUUUUUGCUAAUAUGAUUGUUUUUAAAUUUUGAUUUUGUUGUUUUAGUUUUGUUGUUAUUGCAGUUUAUGUCCUAGUUUGUUGUUUUGUUUCAUGUUUUUCUAAUUGAUAGCAAGAUAAACAUGAAGCUGUGGGAAUGAAAAAAAGGUACAGGGGCAAAAAGACAUUUGGAACGUUAUUCCGCAUACGUUGAAAUAUAUGUUUUCAAGUGUAUUGACACUGAUGUUUCCAUUUUAAUACAUUUUAAUCUAAAAUUAAAUAAUCCUGUGUCAUUAGAGACGUAGGCUCCUUCUAGCUUUGUGUUCUACAAUCCCUAAGUCAGAUGUUCCAUUGAUGGGUCACAAAUGGCUAUUUGACUCCAAGAAUGGAAUUUUAUGCAAGGGAGAAAGGAGGAGGAAUGGGAGGGAUUAAAAGGACUUUCCUGGAAGUUUUGUCCAAAUGAUUUCAAUUUAUUUUUCAUUGAUCUGUGUGAUAUGGUUUGGCUCUGUGUCCCCACCCAAGUCUCAUCUUGAAUUGUACUCCCAUAAUUCCCAUGUGUUGUGGAAGGGACCCAAUGGGAGAUAAUUUGAACCCUGGGGGGGUGGUUUUCCCCAUACACUUCUCAUUGCAGGGUAUAAGUCACACAAGAUCUGAUGCAGGGGUUUCCGCUUUUGCAUCUUCCUCAUUUUCUCUUGCCGCCACCAUGUAAGAAGUGCCCUUCACCUCCUGCCAUGAUUCUGUGGCCUCCCCAGGCUUGUGGAACUGUAAGUCCGAUUAAGCCUUUUUUCUUCCCAGUCUCGGAUAUGUCUUUAUCAGCAGCAUGAAAAUGGACUAAUACACAGUGUAUCUGUAAGGGAUGACUGGAAAACUGUUUUCUAGCUGAAUAUACCUUAGGGAUCUGUUAGUGAGAUAAAAAUUCAAAAUGGAUAUUGUGUAGGCCGCUAGCACUGUUUGUCACAGCAGAUAUGCCUAACUUCUACUUGACUUUUCAUUUACUAUAAAUGCUGGACUUCGUAUUAAUGACUAUUCAAUUUUCUUUCAUAAUUUCAACCUAGAAGAAUACAUUUGCACCUUGAUUCAAUCAUCUUUUAUAUGAGCUGAACUUCCCAACUUUCUGUCAUUUGAAAAUUUAAUGAGCAAGCUUUCUCUUGCUUUACUCAACUCUAUGACCUAAUGUAAAGGAAAAACUAUCAUGAAAACAAAAAUAAGAAGAAAAUGUAAAUCACUGCUUCUUUCUAUAUCCAGGACACUGAAAAGGAUUUACAUGACUUUUUAUGAGACUUUUAAAACUUAUUCUGGUGGUGGGUGCCUGUAAUCCCAGCUACUCAGGAGGCUGAGACAGGAGAAUUGCUUGAAUCCAGGAGGUGGAGGUUGCAGUGAGCCGAGAUCCCACAACUGCACUCCAGCCUGGGCAGCAAGAGCAAAACUCCUUCUCACCAAAAAGAAAAAAAAACCCAAAAAAACCUAUUCUAAUGACAAUUUUUUUUUUUUGAGUUUUGUUUCUGAAUGGAUGGGUGGAAAAUGGAGAAACCUAGAACUGGGAGAAAGACAAUAAAUGUGAGAAGCAAUAAAACAGAGGAAAGCAGGCCUCUUAACAUGUUGGAAGGCUGAGGUAGAUAUAAAUUGUGAAAUUCUCCAUAGUUGGAUAUCUUAGGGUGUUUUAUAAUAAUAAUGUUUACUACUUAAUUUUUAGUUAUUAUUUUAUUUCGGUGAUAUAGUUUCCCACUUCUCACUCAUUAACUUCCAAUUUUCAGGGUCUGAUACACACAGCAGCUUUCUGUUUUAGACAACAUUUUCCACAGGGCUGAGAUUCAAAGAUAAUUCAUGACAACCACAAAAGGUAGAAAGGGAAGUAAGACAUGGAGAUUAAUGCAGCAACGGAUGUGGGAAUUAUUAGUUGAACAUUAGUGUUUACUCCCACCUUAUCUUCCAAAAUCCUUACAUAUAUUGAGAAGAGCACUUUCCCCAGUAUUGGUGGAUGUGUUCUUGAAUCAUUUCCUUUAGACAUUGAGGAAAAUAUGACCACAGAAAGGUGGAAGACAAGGGCUAUUCACAGUGUAGAAUAUACACCUAUUUAAAAUGGAACCUGUAAACCAAAAAGUAUAAAACAAGUCUCAAUUAAUUUAGAAGUUUAUUUUGCCAAAGCUAAGGGCAUGUGCAUAACACAGUCUCAGGAGAUCCUGAGAACAUGUUCCCAAGGUGGUUGGGCUACAGCUUGGUUUUAUAUGUUAUAGAGAGACAUAAACGUCAAUCAAUACAUGGAUGGUACAUUGGCUCAGCCCUAAAAGGCAAGACAACUGGAAGCAAUUGUGUAGGGAUGGGGGUGUGGCUUCCAGGUGAUUAAAAGAUUUUCUAACUGGCAAUUGGUUGAAAGAGUUUAUCUAAAGACUAGAGUCAAUAGAAGGAGGGAGUGUUUGGACUAAGAUAAGAGGUUUUGGAGACCAAGGUUUUCAUUCUGCAGGGGAAGCCUCCAGGUAGCCGGCUUCAGAGAGAAUAGAUUGUAAAUGUUUCUUAUCAGACGUUAAAAGAUGCCAGGCUCUUAGUUAAUUCUCUCCUGGAUCAGGAAAAAGACCUAGAAAGGAAGAGAAUUCUCUACAGAAUGUAGAUUUUCCCCACAAAAGACAGCUUUACAGGGUCAUUUCAAAAUAUGUCAAAGAAACAAAUUCGGGGGUGAAAUACUUUGAUUUCUCUCGGGGCCUGCUGUCUGUCAUGUCGGUAUAUUAUUGUAACAAAGCGUCUGCUUUGUCAGUCUUAAGUUCUCUGUUUUAAAUGUUAGUGCUGGUCAAUCAUGCCUGAAUUCCAAAGAGAAGUGGGGUGUAAGGAAGGCAUGUCUGACCACCCAUUUGCACCAUGGCCUGAACUGGUGUUUCAGAUUGACUUUGGAAAGCCCUUGGCCAAGAGGAGGGUCCAUUUGGUUGGCUGGGAAGGCUUAGAACUUUAUUUUUAGUUUACAGAGCCAAGCCAGAAAUUCGCGACCGUUUAUCAGAGAUUUUACAGGAUAUCUUGAGACAUUAGCAGAAACUUGAAGAUUUUAUCAGUUAUGUAUUAAUGUGAUUACCAUGCUUAUACUUCUUUAUUCUGUCUCCUCUGCUAGAUUCUAAACUCUCAGGACAGGGAUAAUACAUAUCUUAUUUAUCUUGGUAAAUCUGGUCUCUAGUAUACCUUAGGCCUUCAGUUAGAAUUUAUUUAGUGAACAUUUGAACUAUGUGAUUCACUGAUAAAGUAUCUCCUAAGUGACCAGCAUUCUUCAUGUACCCUUACAGUAAGAAUUACAUUUACCCACAUAUUUACUUUUAAUACACAAGUCUAUUUCAAUACUAUUGAAGUAAUCUUUAAGUUAAGUGAGGCCCAACAGAAAGUACUUGAAAACACACAUAUGUAAAUAUGGUGAUACUGAGGGCUUUUAAGUCACUAAGUUAAUGAUUCUCAAGGUGUGGUCACUGGUCCAGCAGCUUCCUUAUCUCCUUAGAAUAUGUUACUAAGGUAGAUUCUCAAGCCACACCCCAGACCUAUGAUUCAGAAACUCUGCAGUGACCCAGUAAUCUGUGUUUUAACAAGCCCUGCAGGUGUUUCAAAUGAACAAUCAAAUUUGAGAACCCGUGCCUUUCUUGAAGAAGUGACUGUGAACAGAUGAUUUCAUAAUAGAAGACAGAAAAAAUAAACUUGAUUAAUGCUUGCUAAGCAUUGGGUACUUUUCCUGAGCUUUCUGUGUCCUCAAAGUUUGUGACUAACUUUAUUUUCAUUUUUAUUUAUUUAUUUUUUGUUUGUUUGUUUGAGACAGAGUCUCGCUCUGUCGCCAGCCUGGAGUGCAAUGGCAUGAUCUCGGCUUACUGCAACCUCCGCCUCCCGGGUUCAAGCAAUUCUCCUGCCUCAGCCUCCCAAGUAGCUGGGACUACAGGCGUGUGCCACCAUGCCCAGCUAAUUUUUGUAUUUUUAGUAGAGAUGAGGUUUCACCAUGUUGGCCAGGAUGGUCUCCCAUCUCUUGACCUUGUGAUCCGCCUGCCUCGGCCUCCCAAAGUGCUGGGAUUACAGGCGUGAGCCACCGCACCCAGCGUUUGUGACUAUCUUUAAAACAUCCAGGACUGUUUGGGUUAGUGAUUGUAAAGUUUGAUCUGUACUUGUAACUGUAUACAGCCAUCCCUUGUCAUACAGGAGGGAUUGUUCCAGGACACUGGAAGAUACCAAAAUCUACUCAUACUCAAGUCCUUCAGCAGACCCUGUCAAACCCAAAUAUAUGAAAAAUUGGCCCUCUGUAUAUGAGGUUUCACAUCCUGCAAAUAUCAAAUUUUCAAUCUGUGUUUGGUUGAAAAAAAAAUCCAUGUAUAAGUGAACCUGCACAGUUCAAACCCAAUUAAUUGUUCAAGGAUCAGCUGUAGUUAUGUUUGUCUCAAGCUAAUAUUGAUCUGUAGAUUUUCUUGGAUGAGUUUUUUAUUUUUGUUUUAUUUGCAUAAGAAAAUGGUCUAAAUAUCCUAAAAUUAAAUGCUUCUUGAUAUAGGUUUGAUAACUGCUUGAUAUUGAUAGCUAACUCAGUUAUAAAUCCCACACAUAAAGUCCAUAACCUUACUUUAAAUUCAUAGUAUAUAUAGCGUUUUGGCCAAAAGAAAGAUACUUUUAUCUGGUCUGUGCUGUCUAAAGUGUUUAUUCUCCCUCCUUUUGGUUAUAUGUUUUAUUUUAUCCUGUACAUUUAUGCUAUCUGUUUGUAUACACAAAUGUAUUUAGAUCAUAAAAAUCAGGUUUCAAGAAUUACACACAUUGUAUUGUAGCUAAUGGGUUUCUGCCCUUUUAUGCAUUCAUGUUUUAAUGAGUUAUUUUCUUGUUGUAUGCUUUAUCACAGGAAAGUCUGUUUUCUCUUGGAAAGUGAGAGUGGCAUAAAUUGUGACUUCUAAAUUUUUUCUAUGAGAAAACAUGGAAACAAUGAAGCCGAUAUGUCAGUAUUCAAAAGUACAAUUAAAUGAUAGUGACUAUCAUGUAUACGUACCAUUUUAAUUAAAAAAUCAUGUGCUCUCUGAUACAUUUGCUCUAUUUUGCAGAAUCUAAAAUGAAAUUGUACUCACUAUAACGUAUUACUUGGUCAUGAAAACUUUCAAUGCUGAGUCCAGGAACACUAAAGCAGGAAUUGAUGAGUGCCAUCAGAAAGCUGUAUCAUGAGCUGCCUGCACUUCUAAAGUGUCCAGUGGAUUUUUAAUCACAUGAGCCUGGAAAUAGGGUUAUGAGAAGAAGCUCAGAGCAGAGCACCGAAAGUGGCCACUACCAGCAUGAAGAGCCCAACAAUUCAAACUGGUGAAGUGAGAAAAACAGAAUGCAGCUUUCAAGGUUCGUUUCAAGCAGUUGGCUUGUGGGACUCUGAGAGAUGCUGCUGCCCAUGACAUGCGGGAAUUAUCAUGAUCAACUACCCAGCUUGGAUUUCACCCAGUGGCCAAGAGCUUUGUGUGGGAGACGGCAAGGGUUGGAUUUUUCAAAAGAGUAAACCAGACCCGUGACCAAGGUGUAGACUAAGAAGUGGAGUCAUGCUUCACACGGCCAUAUCAUGCUGGCAGCCAUUCCUGGGUCUGGCUGUGGUGUUAAUCUUCAUGGGAUCCACCAUUGGCUGCCCCGCUCGCUGUGAGUGCUCUGCCCAGAACAAAUCUGUUAGCUGUCACAGAAGGCGAUUGAUCGCCAUCCCAGAGGGCAUUCCCAUCGAAACCAAAAUCUUGGACCUCAGUAAAAACAGGCUAAAAAGCGUCAACCCUGAAGAAUUCAUAUCAUAUCCUCUGCUGGAAGAGAUAGACUUGAGUGACAACAUCAUUGCCAAUGUGGAACCAGGAGCAUUCAACAAUCUCUUUAACCUGCGUUCCCUCCGCCUAAAAGGCAAUCGUCUAAAGCUGGUCCCUUUGGGAGUAUUCACGGGGCUGUCCAAUCUCACUAAGCUUGACAUUAGUGAGAAUAAGAUUGUCAUUUUACUAGACUACAUGUUCCAAGAUCUACAUAACCUGAAGUCUCUAGAAGUGGGGGACAAUGAUUUGGUUUAUAUAUCACACAGGGCAUUCAGUGGGCUUCUUAGCUUGGAGCAGCUCACCCUGGAGAAAUGCAACUUAACAGCAGUACCAACAGAAGCCCUCUCCCACCUCCGCAGCCUCAUCAGCCUGCAUCUGAAGCAUCUCAAUAUCAACAAUAUGCCUGUGUAUGCCUUUAAAAGAUUGUUCCACCUGAAACACCUAGAGAUUGACUAUUGGCCUUUACUGGAUAUGAUGCCUGCCAAUAGCCUCUACGGUCUCAACCUCACAUCCCUUUCAGUCACCAACACCAAUCUGUCUACUGUACCCUUCCUUGCCUUUAAACACCUGGUAUACCUGACUCACCUUAACCUCUCCUACAAUCCCAUCAGCACUAUUGAAGCAGGCAUGUUCUCUGACCUGAUCCGCCUUCAGGAGCUUCAUAUAGUGGGGGCCCAGCUUCGCACCAUUGAGCCUCACUCCUUCCAAGGGCUCCGCUUCCUACGCGUGCUCAAUGUGUCUCAGAACCUGCUGGAAACUUUGGAAGAGAAUGUCUUCUCCUCCCCUAGGGCUCUGGAGGUCUUGAGCAUUAACAACAACCCUCUGGCCUGUGACUGCCGCCUUCUCUGGAUCUUGCAGCGACAGCCCACCCUGCAGUUUGGUGGCCAGCAACCUAUGUGUGCUGGCCCAGACACCAUCCGUGAGAGGUCUUUCAAGGAUUUCCAUAGCACUGCCCUUUCUUUUUACUUUACCUGCAAAAAACCCAAAAUCCGUGAAAAGAAGUUGCAGCAUCUGCUAGUAGAUGAAGGGCAGACAGUCCAGCUAGAAUGCAGUGCAGAUGGAGACCCGCAGCCUGUGAUUUCCUGGGUGACACCCCGAAGGCGUUUCAUCACCACCAAGUCCAAUGGAAGAGCCACCGUGUUGGGUGAUGGCACCUUGGAAAUCCGCUUUGCCCAGGAUCAAGACAGCGGGAUGUAUGUUUGCAUCGCUAGCAAUGCUGCUGGGAAUGAUACCUUCACAGCCUCCUUAACUGUGAAAGGAUUCGCUUCAGAUCGUUUUCUUUAUGCGAACAGGACCCCUAUGUACAUGACCGACUCCAAUGACACCAUUUCCAAUGGCACCAAUGCCAAUACUUUUUCCCUGGACCUUAAAACAAUACUGGUGUCUACAGCUAUGGGCUGCUUCACAUUCCUGGGAGUGGUUUUAUUUUGUUUUCUUCUCCUUUUUGUGUGGAGCCGAGGGAAAGGCAAGCACAAAAACAGCAUUGACCUUGAGUAUGUGCCCAGAAAAAACAAUGGUGCUGUUGUGGAAGGGGAGGUAGCUGGACCCAGGAGGUUCAACAUGAAAAUGAUUUGAAGGCCCACCCCUCACAUUACUGUCUCUUUGUCAAUGUGGGUAAUCAGUAAGACAGUAUGGCACAGUAAAUUACUAGAUUAAGAGGCAGCCAUGUGCAGCUGCCCCUGUAUCAAAAGCAGGGUCUAUGGAAGCAGGAGGACUUCCAAUGGAGACUCUCCAUCGAAAGGCAGGCAGGCAGGCAUGUGUCAGAGCCCUUCACACAGUGGGAUACUAAGUGUUUGCGUUGCAAAUAUUGGCGUUCUGGGGAUCUCAGUAAUGAACCUGAAUAUUUGGCUCACACUCACGGACAAUUAUUCAGCAUUUUCUACCACUGCAAAAAACAAAAGAAAAAAUAAAAAAGAACAACCUACAGUGUAGGAUUUACAUAUUAAAAAGACACAUUUGUCUAAAACAUACUCUACAGAAAAAUUUGUAUCUAUGAUUAUCAUUUGUUAAAGCCUUGCAUCAUACCAUAUUGUUGGUUCAGUACCACAAAGAGAUCAAUAUAUUCUUUUCUUCCUUUUUUGAAACAUAUAUGCUGUACAUGUUUUAAAGCAAUAUGAAUGAGAGGUUGUGCUUUUAGUUACUCACCACUAUAGAUCCAAGUGUGAUUUCACCUUCCGUUACCUACAGAUGACCCUGAGACUAGAUCCCUGGAGUUAUGGGCGGAGAUAUUUUGAGAGAUGUGUUUGUCUGAUGUAGGAUGCCAAGAAACAGGACCCAAGGCAAAACUGCUCAACUCUGUUAACUUCUGUUACUAUAAAUAAAGGCAUGUGCCUAGUUUUGAUACAGAAUGGAAUAUUUUUUAUACUUGUAAUAAUAUCACACUGGACCAGUUUACUGUAAACAAAGCCCUUGGUUUCUCCAGAAGGUGGUACACCACUAGAUGUACCUGUAAAAUGCAAGGUAGGUGUUAAUAAUGAAAAUGAUUCAUUUAAUCACUCCUUGAUUUUACUUUCCACAGUCACUAUUAGCGGGUUAAUAGAAAAUGGAAGAAGAGGUAAUGGUUACAAAUAACCAUAGGAUAAUAUUCACCAGUGGCUAAGAUCAAGAAUUCAGAUGUUCAAAAGCUCUCUGAAUAAGAAAGAGUUCUUCUCAGAUGCCAACACAAACCAGGGUGAUACAUACAUAACAUGAUGUUAAUGCAAACAACGAUUUGUUUAAAACAUGAUAGCUGCCUGCAUGCUAGAUUGCUGCUAGUCAAGGGAACAUCUAGCUACUGCCACUCUGAUGUUCUCUACUUGAAUACUGUACACACAAUAUUACCUUGAAUAGACAACUUCAGGGUUUCUUCCUGCUUCCUUACCAAUUAGAUUUUGGUUUUUUCUUUGAAAAUUAUCUUGUAUAAUAAAGAGGAAUUUGUCUUGUUUUCUAAGAACUGAGAAAAAACAAGGUGGAUUAAAAACCAUUUAGUGUUUUUUUUCUCCACUGAGGAAAAAGCAAGGUUAUAGCCCCAUAAAUAUGUCAAGUUGUGCUGAUUUUUUUUCCUCUCUCUGACCCAAGGAUACUUAUCCAAUUCAGUUUGUAUUAAUGACUGUUACUCAAAGUUAAACAUCCCAGUUUUUAAAAACUGAUGUCAUGCCGUGACCACCAGUCAUCUGGUUCAGAGCAGGCAUAGUUUCAUUUGGCUAAAUGUUCAGUGAAUGACUUUCAAAGCAUAUGGUUAUGUGAUCUGAGAAAGAAUUGAAUGUGGACUGUGUUCAUGCAAUGUCAAAUAUUUAAUCAGCAUAGAACUGAUAGGAAAUAUCUAUACUUUUCCUAUUUCAAGAGGGAUCUGAAAAUAGGUCAUGUUUUUAAUAACAUGUAAGCUGGAGUAGAAAGUCUCUGGGGUUUGCUUCUUGACAUAUUGGAUUGGCGGGUUGACAUUCAAAAGGCUGGCUUUUUAGUUUGAAAUUUGAAAAUUUGAAAUUUUGAAGAACUUUAAUAAAAUUAAAUUGACCCCAAUAAAAGUAGGAUAAGCCCAGAAAUUAUUUUGCCAAUCAGAUAGCAACAGAGUUAAACCCAUUUCUCCCCUAAUAAAGGGUGGAAAAUAUGAUGAAAGAUUGAAGAAUUGCCUGUUCAAGCCAUUUUUCAUUUGACUUUUCUGAUGACUAUCAUAGAUCUUUUAGAAUUUUAUUUUCCAUUUGUGCCAAAUACCUUAUAUCAAACAAUGCAAAUCAAGCUCUGCUGCAAACUCUAUCACAAAUCCAACUUGUGUGCAAAUGGAAUGGGGUCUUUCAAAUUUAAAAAUGAACUGUUAGAGAUUUCAAAAAAACUUCCAAAAGUUAAUAGAAACUAUUUUGCAGCAUUGUGUGAAGUGUAGUAUUCAACUAAUUGUCAUAAAAGAGAAACAUUGAGCAAUUAAUAAGAGGGCUUUGUGAUUUUCACUGCUCUUUUGUCAAAAUAAAAGUUGGCCAAAAACAGCUGAGUGAAAUGAAAUUGGAUUAAAAUGUACCCAUCCAUGAAAAAGAUUUAGUUAAAAGAUUUUGUUACUAUUCAUUUUAUUGGAAGAAAAGAGAAUGGAUUUUCUCAGCGGUCCCAUACUCUGAUCUAUGGAAUAAUAGUUAUUUAAGAUAUUUCUAAGCAUUCUUCCAAAAAAGUCCUGUUGACCAGUCUAUCAGGGAAAUGCAUUCUGUAACCACCUUUAGAGAUUCAAAAUCUAUAUGAGCCUAAUAAAUCCUCUGAAAAGUCCUGUAAACAGGAAUCCUGUUUAAUAUUGUUUAUCUUCAGGCUUCACUAAUUUAUAUGAGCAGAAAGCACUUCUUUUCGUGCUAUAACUGUUAACAUUUUCAAAAACUAGAGCUCCAUAGAACCCCGGUUGGUCUACUUCAGACUAGAGUAAUACUCUUGUGACGUAUUCCUAAACCUAAUGUUUCCAAUAAGAGUAAAAUUACUGUUUGAAUUGGCCUCCGAUAGACUACCAAAAAAAUAUUGACUGUGUCAGUGCUUAGAUCAUAAAAGUAUAUUGACCAGAUAUUUUCAGGGGAAUUGGCUACUUUUUGCCUGAAGCAUCCAUCAUAGCAAUGGAUUAAGAGGUAAUUGAAUAGACAUUUAAUUUUCUACACUCUCACUAUCUGAGCAGAUCUUGGGUUCUUUUUGUGCGUGCAAAGCUCUGGUAUCCAUUGAGUGAAACGCUGGUGCUUUAGUACUCAGUUUCACAAAAGGGUUAAUGAAUUUUCCCUCAUGGCUUCUGAUUACCUCUUUGUUAUAUCAACUAGACCAUGGUAGAGCAUAACAGCUCAUACCAGCACAGGGGCCAACUACUCACUUAAAUAUGACAUCUCUGAGUCAUUUUCUUCCCAGAGGCUUUGUUUCAAAGUAUCCCAGAAAGAAAUACUGUUGUUUGACUCAGCAUUUCACUCCAGUUGGUUUUCAUUCCACUCUGGUUUUGCUCAACUUUCUCAGAAAUUUUGCUUGUUACUGACAACUCCCUAGUAGGAAAAACACAUUCAGAAGUUGCCCUACAGUAUUUAGGAUGGAUUCUUUUUUCAUUAUUCUGUCAAAUAUUCUGUGUUCCUCAGUUCUUACAGGAGUCCAGAAGUUGCAGUCUUCUGUGACUCUUUAAAAAAUGAUUAUUUAAAUGUCAUUUGCAUUGAGGCCUGACUUUUGUCACUUUACUCUGGUACAAACACAUGUAUUUUUAUAUCAGAGGAACAAAAGAGAGAAUGUGAUCUUGGAGAAAUAAAAUUGAGUAAAGUCCCAUGUAAAUUAACUUGUAUUUCCAGGGUCUCUCUUCAUCUCUGUGUCAAGACAUUUGUUUUAACUUCAGGGGAUGUACUCAGAAGCCAUUCAACACUGCAUAUGUCUUGAGGGUUUCUAGGAAAGAAAAAAAUUACAUAAUUUUCAGCUUAGAAGUCUAAGACCAAACAUAAAGAUAUAUCAAGACUUUAAAGAAGGUUGGAGGCAGACACUUGACCCAUGUUAAUCCUGUUUUCUUUCUUGCCAAUUUUUGUAGUUAUCUCCUACCUGAAGAAGAAUCAGAGAUUAUGUUCUUCCUUGACUUUCACUGAAGUCCUUUUUAUACCUUUUUUCUAUGACCCAGUCACCUAUAUCUCACAUGAGCUAUCCCAAAUGGAUUCUGUGGCAUCUGAAUCUAGUAACAAAACCUUUGGGACCAAAGGCAUUCAUUCUACUCAGCACUUAGGUAAAGACUUAUUAUCUCUAUUACUAUAAUUAACAUUCCCUGUUUGUUAGACUCAUACAUCAUGUGCCUGGUUAUUUCCAUUGAUUUUCCACCGUUGGCUUUGGGAGCACCUUUUAAUUCCUUUCAGCUAGAACCCUUGAUGUUUUUCUGAUUGAGGAGUUUGGGAAUUAUUCUGCCUUUGGGUAUAGAAAGUUUUGAGGAAUGAAAUAUUAUUUGUUUGAUUUUUGAAUUUUCUAUUUUCGUUAGGCAACAGAGGGUGUUUUCUGGUACUUUGGCAAACACUUGACAUGAAUCUCUCAGUGAUGCUCCCCUUUUCACCUUCAAAAGCCAUUCCCAAAAGAGCCUUCUCAUUUACAUUCCAGCUGGGAAAGGACAGCUUUACAACAUAGGUGUACAGGAUAAAAUGAUAGCUGAUUGCUGUGCUCUUUAGCUCAAUUAACCUAAUAAACACUGGGUCCAGGGGCCAUAUGUCUAGGCUUGCAAGGUUUAGCCAAGUAAACAAGGUUUUAAAUCAACAAUUAAUGACAGGUUUUCGACUCUGAAGUUGGUUUGCCUGUUUGGAGAACAGUAUGUGUAACUGCAUGUCUUCUCAAAAAGGUAGGGACUAGAACUUCCUUAUCUUAUGUGAGAUUUUUAACAAAUGGUCUAGGAUAAAAUGUGUCCAACAACAACAAAAUACAUAAUUAAGAUGUUUGUAAAAGGUUUAUUUUUCUAAAAUAGGAUUGGGGCUGAUGUUACUCUUUCCAAAUUUGGGAGUUUGAUCAGGACAAGCUUGCAUGUGCCCCAGACUGCCCUUUCUCAAGUUUACCAAGGUCUUUAAUACCUCUUCUCCCUCCCUGAUCCCCUUCUCCCUGGAGAACAUCCUGAAUAGGAAGGAGAAAAAGAGCAGGAACUAAAGUCCCCUGAGACAGCCCACAGAAGGAGAAAAGCUUUGGUAUUCCCCCACAUUCUUGCCUCCUUUCCUGAUGCAGCAAUUGAAAUGAUCCUUCACUCUCUGCCUACUUACCACUGUCACUUCUCAGCUGCUGCCAUCCUCAUCAAUGAACGCUCUCUCCAGGGAUAAGUCUUCUUUCAUUGGUAACUGAGAUUCUUGGGUAAUUGUUAAACUGGAAAUUGCUUUAAAAAAAAAAAACCCUCCAGCUAUCUCACAUAACACUUUAAAAGUUAAGACUUACCAUUCACAUAAUCACAAGCUGACAGCAAUCUGCAGGUUGAGUGAUUCUGAUUUUUUUUCCUCUCCCUUCCAGAAGCAGGUGGGUUGAUAUAAUGCCAGCCUUAAAUAGAAAGCUUUAUUUAUAGCCUUAGCAGAAUGAGAAAAGAGCUGGCAUAAUCAAGAGAGUACUUCACAUUUUAAAGAAGACUUUACCUUUAAUAUGCAAAAUAGUCAUUAGAAGACAACAAAAAUGCAAAUUUAUGUUUUACUAAAUUGCUUAACUAUAUUCCAAUAAAGUUCAAAAGAUAACUGUCCAUACUGAAGAUGGGUCAGCCAAAGACUUUAUGCCUGUUCUAAAAGGACCAAAAAAAAGCAGAAAUUUGGUUGCCAUGUUAACUUUAUGUUGUUGCACACCUCCUAUUCUAAAUUGCUUUAAUAUCUUUACACUGCAAUAUAUUGAGUAAAAUCAACAAUAUAAGAUAAAUAAUAAACAGGAGAUUAAUUCAGACUUGCAAAAAAAAUUUUUCAUUCUUUACAAUGUAUGUCCAGCAGCAAAAUGAUGUAUAUACAUAUCUGUGUGAUAACAAGAGAUUGGAAUUGGCAUGAACAAACUUUGCAUAGAGGCUGUUUGGAAGAAAACAUGCUGUUUUUCUCCCCAGUUACAAAAUCAGGUAUAUCAUAAAAACCUGAGUUGCUUCAUAACAAGACAGUUGUUUUCAGGUUUUUUCCAUGUGGUAUAGAAUACCCCAAAUCAUAAUUAAUUUCUAUUGUUUAUAUAUACAUAUAUAAAUAUGUGGGGAAGGGUGGUUAGAUUUUUUUGUGUUUAAAUUAUAACCGUUUUAAAAGUUGAUAAGCCUGAGCAGGAGAAAAAGAGACAGAAUGUGUAUCUGUGUUUUCCUUUAAUGUCUUUUAUCAAAAUCCUAUUUUGAGAAUAUCCCAUGAUUGAAAGUUAAUAACCAAGAACCUAACAAAACUUUUCGUAAAAAAUGCCUGAAAGUUUUUGUUUUCAAAAAAUUAAUGCUAAUGACAAAAGUAUCUUGAUUUAGGUUUGCAUCUCUUUAGCUAUUGGUUAAUUGUUGUGGGCAUGUUUUUUUUAACAUGUAAAAACAAAUUAACUUAUUAACAUGUAAAAUAAGUUAAGAAAACAUGUUUUCUUUUCGGAUGAAAGGGCUUAAGCAUCUGACAUCUCAGUUAAAUUCACUGAAGUAUUAAUAAGAAAUGCAAUAUGAGACAAUCGGAGUCGUAUAAAAAUAUUUUCUUAUUGAGAGAAGUAGGUUAUAUGAGUCUCACAGGGAACGUGAGGUAUCACUGUAUUAAUUAGUAAUCCCCAAUACUGUCAGAGAUGAAGCAGGUCCAGUGGAAUCUCAUUCAAAUGCUAAGGUGAGUGGAGAUAACUCACAGAGGAAUCAAAAGACAGGCUAUCCAGUUACAUAAAGUUACAAAGGGGUCAUAGUUCAACCUGAUGGGCAUCCAAAUUUAUGUAAUAUCAACCACACUCUAAAGAUAUUCUACUUUUGUGGAGUUAAAUCCUGUAUCACUUGCAAAAGUAUCCCAAAUUCAUGUGACUUAAUAACAUAAGCAAGUAAUGGGCAUAACUUAAGGCGUAAGAUCUAUUUGAGCAAGAACUGAAGGGUUCAGCAAGCCAUACAUACAACACCACCCUCUAGUUUUUCUUUCUGAGUUAGCCUUCACUCAGCCAAAUGAUUCAAAACAUUGUGUCAAGUAGGAAGCCACAAAAAAAAUAAAAAGAGAAACAACUUUAGUCUUCAAGCAAAUUGAAAAAAGGGAAAGAGAAAAUUGUCUAGUGUUAAAGAGGAAAUGAAUUGAAAAUUUUUAAACUCCUCUUGGGCUGAGAGUGAAGGUGCCCUCUCUUUACCUUUCGUACUUGAGGGAAUGGGCUUUAGAGAGAUGUGUUCAGGCAGGUGUCAUCAUCUAGGGUAUCAUCUUUACUCCCUGUGGCUCAUUAGAUGGCUUCCAGUGAAGGAGGAGGAGGUAGAGAAGGAAGCAGAAAGCUGACAGUCAUGGUACCUGAAAGUCACAUUGUUAGAGAACAAGAAAGUCCGGGAUUCAUCUCCAGGAAGCAAUAAACACACAAAUACUGAGACUGUUAGCAAGAAACCAGAAAAGGUCCCUUUGCUAUUCUUCUUUUCUUUUCUUUUCUUUUUUGAGUCUCACUCUGUCAACAGGCUGGAGUACAGUGGCACAAUCUCGGCUCACUGCAACCUCCCCGUCCCGGGUUCAAGAGAUUCUCCUGCCUCAGCCUCCCCAGUAGCUGGGAUUACAGGCACCCACCACCACACCCGGCUAAUUUUUGUAUUUUUUUAGUAGAGACAGGGUUUCACCAUGUUGGCCAGGAUGGUCUCGAUCUCCUGACCUCGUGAUCCGCCCACCUCGGCUUCCCAAAGUGCAGGGAUUACAGACAUGAGUCACUGCACCCGGCCUGCUGCUAUUUAAUUGCAAAAUGAAAAGCUUGCCCCUAGAGAGAGAAUUUCUUGAAAAUGUUCUGUUAAUGCCAGAGCUGCUCUGGUCAGAGUCACAUCUCUAACAGUGGGCUUUUAUUUUAUGCUAGUAAAUCAGUAAGACUAAAACAAAGGGCCAUUUCCCAUAAGCAUAGUUUUGAAUGUGUUGGGUAGACAUCUCGCCAAUUAAUAUUAGGAGUUAGCUUGUCCAGUAAACUCACCAAUCAGGGAUAAGAUGAUCCCAAUACUUCAGAACUUGUACUUAAACAAUGGGAAGAAGAUAAUAUAAUGAACUCGAAGCUAAACAUACUUUUAACUCAGUGGCCUGGCUUCUAGCUCUGCACCUUAAAGACUUUCUGGUCAUGUAUUACUUCAUAAAUUUAGAAGUUCUUCAUAGUUCUGUGUUUCUGUUUCUGUUUGGUUUCUUCUUCCUUUCAUUUUUCUCAGUCAUGAGCAUACUGCCCUUGCUAGAUGGCUGUUAAUGUUUUUGUGUUGUUUGAUACAGUCGAAAUAAAAAUUAGGAGUUUCUACCGACUCCCUUCAAGGCAGAUAAGCUUAUUGUACAACCCUAUAUUCUUUUCUUAAUUACUUCAUUAUCAGACCUAAAACACAGGACAUGAAGAUUAAUGUGGAAUAAAGCCAAGUUAAGGAGAAAAGUGAGAAACCUGAGGGGAAAUUUACCUACUAUUUCUGCCACUGACUGGUGGAAAAUCUGAAAACACUGGCUUCUAGGGCUUGUCACACUGGUGCCUUUCAUCAACUCUUAUAAAUAACUAAAUGCAAAAAUUAUGACCCUCUAUCAAAAAAUAAAGGAUUGGGAAGGAGAUCGCUUAUUACAGCUAUGCAGGUAUUGUUUUAUUCUAUAACGCUGUCAUUGGCAAAUCAGGACAUGUCAAUAAAUCUCUCAAAGUAGUAUAUGUAUAUUAAUGGCAGAAUGACACGUAUAUACAUAUCUAUUACUAAGAACCAUCUGGGGAAAAAAAUAAGAAAAUUUAAAAAAUAAAAAAAGAUAAGGCAGGUGGAAAAUAUGUGGAUUCUCCCUAUUCUAUUUGUCUGCUAAAAAAACUAAGACCUCACCUGAAUCACCAGAGUCAGGGUCUCAGAAAUGAAAACCCAAGGAGAGUCUCUACAAAAAGAACAGACUGCUAGAGAGGAUACCUCUUUGAUUAAAAUACCUAAAUCUUUUAUGUGAUUGUGAAAGUUAUAUCUAUAGUGAAUAAUUUUGUAUUGUCACAUUGGGAGAUAAAUUUGUUUACCAGAUCCCCAUCUAAGGCAGAAAUAACAUUUAUGUGAACCCUUUUCUAACUGCAGCAUCACUAUUCAUAUUAUUUCCAAGCACAAGAGAUCAAGUAUGCUAGUACCAUAGCACAGAGGCAAUUCACCACAUCUAGCCUAUUCCUUUAGCCAUGGGCUAUUAGCUGGAUGUACAAAAGACUAACAGGUUACAUCCAUUCUAUACAUGCAGGGAUUUCAUAAAAGUUAAACACUUCUUCAAACCUGCACACACAAAUCCAUACUGUGGCAUCCAGAGUUUCUUUAAGCCUCACACUGUAUCAGUACAAACAUCCUACAGGGAAUUAAUUCACUGAGCACAGAACAAAUGUGUAAUGCAAAGAGAUUACCAAGUCACCUCCACCACCUUGAUUUAUAUAAGCUCUUCUGUUUUAGCAACACCUGGAGAAUCCAGUGGUCUGUGCUUCAGUGGUCUCAAGAGCUCUUCAUGGCAGUUCUGUAAGAAAGUUGCUGGCUUUAACGCAGGGCUGGUUUCAAUAUAGGGCAGCUGUUUUCUGCUGUGAGUCUUCUGGAGGAAAAAGAAUGGGUUCACGGAAACUGAAAGUAACUGAAAAAUGUAUCCUGGCUGGUGAGUGUAGGAAGAGUAGUUCAUUGUUCUAAUGGUUGAAUAUAUUUCAAAAGAACAUUUAAUAAGAAUUGGAGAACACAAGCAUUUCAAAUAAAUGGCAAUGAUCAUAUGAGCAUGUGUAAGAGAAUUUAAUUGCAGAGGAAAAUGGAUGAUUAUGCAUAUCACACUGCCUCUAAUAUUGAUCUUGAGUUGGUUUCCAAAUUGAUAAGUAAAUACAUUCUAUAUUGAAAAUCAUUUUAAAUGUCUAUUUAUAUCUUUUAAAUAUUGCCAAUAAUUAGCUUAAAUACAUGCCCUCAAAAUAUUCAGGAAUCUACUCGGUCCUUUCCUUCUCAUCCUUGAUUAGAAGUUAAAAAUCAGAUUUCUCUAGCUUUGUUUUAAAAGAUACAGAAAAUUUAAUUUUCCAAUUAUCCAAGCACAAUCUCCUUUCAUUCAUUUACUCAUUUAAUUAUGCAACAUCUACUGAGUAUCCAUUAUCAUAGUAAUCGAGCUGCCCGUCACUGAAGUCAUUAUCAAACUGUGGUUUAAACCUUAGCUCUGUGUUUCUCCACAUUAACUCCUUUGGCUUCCAUAUUGAUUGCAACUUGUGUCUCAUUCUGUCAUCUAAAUCAUGUGGUUUAGAGAUAGGCCUUAGUGUCCACCUGGCCAGGCACAAGUCUGGCGUUAAGGACCUACCUGCUUUAAUGAUCCACUCUCAGGGAGUCAGAACAGUUAAGUACUAAAAAGACAAGGAUCUGGAGUGAGAGUCCCUAGGGCUAUGUCACUGGAUUCAUGUUUCUUUAUGGGCAAGCUACUUAACAUCUCUGCAUCCCCAUCUCUCAAAAUAACCAUAACACUACCUACCUCACAAGGGUGCUGUGAGGCUUACCAUGAAAAGCAUGAGGAAAUGGUAUAUAGAAUUGGGGACCUAGUAGAAAGGUGCUACAGGAUUAGAGUAACUAGAUAUCAUUGAGUAUGAACCCUGCUUUCCCUGGGAGCCCCAGGUUUGCCAGAAUAUGUCUAAUCUCUUUACGGCUAGAAUCUAAAAUGGUGUUGGCCAUCGAUUGGCUUAGGUUAUCUUUAAUGUCAUUGACUUUUACAAAAUUCGUAACGACACCUCUUUCUCAGAGAGAUGCUGGAUUGGAAAAAUUAUUAAAUUAAUUUUAACAAAGGAGAACAAAAAUGAUUCACUUCCAGGUGCUGGGUGUGGCGGAACAGUUAUUUAUUUCAAUAUGAAACAAGAGUUUGAAUGGAUAUCUUCAAGGGGAUGCAUUUUAUUGGAGACAUUUAUUGCCUGGGGCUUUCUGUUUUCAGUCUGACUCCCCAGCUUUCUGUAUCAUUGUUUUAACAUACAUCCCCUUUUCUCCUUUAUUGGAAGAGAAGCUAUAAUUCUCCUCAUUUCAUGAUAAUCCUUUUCAGUCUGUUUUGCUCAAAGGACAAAUUCUUUUCAACAACUAUUGUAAUUAUUUUCUUAGAGGGCCAUUUUUAAUUGCCGUAUUGUUUAGCUAAGCCCUAUUGUCUUGGUGUCCUUCAAAACUGUCAGUUGCAUUAAAAUAUAGGGGUGGGAGGGGAGCUGAUAAGCACAUUGUUGUAAUUGAUUUGUAUGUUUGAAUUGUCUUAUCAGAAAACAAGGUUAUGAAUUUCAUCUGUUGAGACACAAAAAUAAAAUACUUUCUUAAAAAA